GCCAGAGUAAGAAUCUUCAGAAGCCUGGUUAGCCAGGGAAUCUCCCCGCAGGCUUUGCCGGGGGACGGUUCCCGUGGAGUUGGGGGUUCAGAUCUAAGAGGGGGCUGCAUUUCGCAGGAGUUGGGGGCCCCGCCCGCUUGGGUGGAGGGAAGAGGAUGGGUAGGGGGUGGUCCUGGAUCCUUCGCAGGUUUGGGGAACUCGAUGCAGCCAAGCUGUAAGGGGGACGAGAGGAAGAGCCAUGGAGUGGAAUCAGACCUUUAUGGGGCUUAGGGGUCAUAUCAUUGGGAGAACUGAGAAGCGCUGAAUUCUCCAGGGGGUGCCUGGAUCCCGAAGUGUCGGGGCCAGGAUGGGGGGACUCGGAUUUCGAUGGGGAUUUGGGGACUGGAUCUCCUCGGUUGAGGCCGGCGCUGCAGGCAGCGGCGGCUGCGCGGUGAACGAGGCGGCCUGCGCGGCGGAGUGCUGAGUCCCGAUCCCCGGCUCUGUCCGGCCCACGGAUCCUCAAGCCCGGGCCCCGGGCCCGGCCCCAGCCUCAGCCCUGAGCGUCUCGGGGCGGAUGGCGCGGGGCGGCGGGGGCGGGCGGUGCUGAGCCCUGCGCGGGCCAUGGCCUCGGCCUGCGGGGCGCCGGGCCCGGGGGGCGCCCUGGGCAGCCAGGCCCCCUCCUGGUACCACCGCGACCUGAGCCGGGCGGCCGCGGAGGAGCUGCUGGCCCGGGCGGGCCGCGAUGGCAGCUUCCUGGUCCGAGACAGCGAGAGCGUGGCGGGGGCCUUCGCGCUCUGCGUCCUGUAUCAGAAGCAUGUGCACACGUAUCGCAUUCUGCCUGAUGGAGAAGAUUUCUUGGCUGUGCAGACCUCGCAGGGUGUGCCUGUGCGCCGCUUCCAGACCCUGGGUGAGCUCAUCGGCCUGUACGCCCAGCCCAACCAGGGCCUUGUGUGCGCCCUGCUUCUUCCUGUAGAGGGUGAGCGAGAGCCGGACCCACCGGAUGACCGGGAUGCCUCAGAUGGGGAGGAUGAGAAGCCCCCGCUGCCCCCGCGCUCUGGCUCCACCAGCAUUUCUGCCCCCACUGGGCCCAGCAGUCCCCUGCCAGCUCCUGAGACUCCCACAGCUCCAGCUGCUGAGAGGGAUGGGGCAGAGGUGCUGGGACAGGUCAGCAGGACCUCCACUGACUUCUUAACCCCUCCCCAAAGUGCUCCCAAUGGGCUGAGCACCGUCUCGCACGACUACCUGAAAGGCAGCUAUGGGCUGGACCUGGAAGCUGUGAGGGGUGGAGCCAGCCACCUGCCCCACCUCACCCGUACCCUCGCUACCUCAUGCCGGAGGCUGCACAGUGAGGUGGACAAGGUCCUGUCAGGCCUGGAGAUCCUGUCCAAGGUGUUUGACCAGCAGAGCUCGCCCAUGGUGACCCGCCUUUUGCAGCAGCAGAACCUGCCACAGACAGGGGAGCAGGAACUAGAGAGCCUGGUGCUGAAGCUGUCAGUGCUAAAGGACUUCCUGUCAGGCAUCCAGAAGAAGGCCCUGAAGGCCCUACAGGACAUGAGCUCCACAGCACCCCCAGCUCCGCAGCCAUCCACACGUAAGGCCAAGACCAUCCCCGUGCAGGCCUUUGAGGUGAAGCUAGAUGUGACCCUGGGUGACCUGACCAAGAUUGGGAAGUCACAGAAGUUCACGCUGAGCGUGGAUGUGGAGGGUGGGCGGCUGGUGCUGCUGCGGAGACAGCGGGACUCCCAGGAGGACUGGACCACCUUCACGCACGACCGCAUCCGCCAGCUCAUUAAGUCCCAGCGUGUCCAGAACAAGCUGGGUGUUGUGUUUGAGAAGGAGAAGGACCGGACUCAGCGCAAGGACUUCAUCUUUGUCAGUGCCCGGAAGCGGGAGGCCUUCUGCCAGCUGUUGCAGCUCAUGAAGAACAAGCACUCCAAGCAGGACGAGCCCGACAUGAUCUCAGUCUUCAUAGGCACCUGGAACAUGGGAAGUGUACCACCUCCAAAAAACGUGACAUCCUGGUUCACAUCGAAGGGUCUGGGGAAGACCCUGGACGAGGUCACAGUGACCAUACCCCAUGACAUCUAUGUCUUUGGGACCCAGGAGAACUCAGUGGGCGACCGCGAGUGGCUGGACCUACUGCGCGGGGGCCUCAAGGAGCUUACGGAUCUGGAUUACCGCCCGAUUGCCAUGCAAUCACUGUGGAAUAUCAAGGUGGCAGUGCUGGUCAAGCCAGAGCACGAGAACCGUAUCAGCCAUGUCAGUACGUCCAGUGUGAAGACUGGCAUCGCCAACACCCUGGGGAACAAGGGGGCUGUGGGCGUCUCCUUCAUGUUUAAUGGCACCUCAUUUGGCUUUGUGAAUUGUCACCUCACCUCGGGAAAUGAGAAGACGGCUCGGAGGAACCAAAACUACUUGGACAUCCUGCGGCUGCUCUCGCUGGGCGACCGGCAGCUCAAUGCCUUUGACAUCUCUCUGCGUUUCACACACCUCUUCUGGUUUGGGGACCUCAACUACCGCCUGGACAUGGAUAUCCAGGAGAUCCUGAACUACAUCAGCAGGAAAGAGUUUGAGCCCCUCCUCAGGGUGGACCAGCUCAACCUGGAGCGGGAGAAGCACAAGGUCUUCCUUCGAUUCAGUGAGGAGGAGAUCUCCUUCCCACCCACCUACCGCUAUGAGCGGGGUUCCCGGGACACAUAUGCCUGGCACAAGCAGAAGCCAACUGGGGUCCGGACCAAUGUGCCCUCAUGGUGUGACCGGAUUCUGUGGAAAUCCUACCCUGAAACUCACAUCAUCUGCAAUUCUUAUGGUUGCACUGAUGACAUCGUCACCAGCGACCAUUCCCCCGUGUUUGGGACAUUUGAGGUUGGAGUUACCUCCCAGUUCAUCUCCAAGAAAGGGCUCUCAAAGACUUCAGACCAGGCCUACAUUGAGUUUGAGAGCAUCGAGGCCAUUGUGAAGACAGCCAGCCGCACCAAGUUCUUCAUCGAGUUCUACUCUACCUGCCUGGAGGAAUACAAGAAGAGCUUUGAGAAUGAUGCCCAGAGCAGUGACAACAUCAACUUCCUCAAAGUGCAGUGGUCUUCACGCCAGCUGCCCACGCUCAAACCAAUUCUGGCUGAUAUCGAGUACCUGCAGGACCAGCACCUCCUGCUCACAGUCAAGUCCAUGGAUGGCUAUGAAUCCUAUGGGGAGUGUGUGGUUGCACUCAAAUCCAUGAUCGGCAGCACGGCCCAACAGUUCCUGACCUUCCUAUCCCACCGUGGCGAGGAGACAGGCAAUAUCAGAGGCUCCAUGAAGGUGCGGGUGCCCACGGAGCGCCUGGGCACCCGUGAGCGGCUCUACGAGUGGAUCAGCAUUGAUAAGGAUGAGGCAGGAGCAAAGAGCAAAGCCCCCUCUGUGUCCCGAGGGAGCCAGGAGCCCAGGUCAGGGAGCCGCAAGCCAGCCUUCACAGAGGCCUCCUGCCCGCUCUCCAGGUUAUUUGAAGAACCAGAGAAACCGCCACCAACGGGGAGGCCCCCAGCCCCACCCCGAGCAGCUCCCCGGGAGGAGCCCUUGACCCCCAGGUUGAAGCCAGAGGGAGCUCCUGAACCAGAAGGGGUGGCGGCCCCCCCACCCAAGAACAGCUUCAAUAACCCUGCCUACUACGUCCUUGAAGGGGUCCCGCACCAGCUGCUGCCCCCGGAGCCACCCUCGCCUGCCAGGGCCCCUGUCCCAUCUGCCACCAAGAACAAAGUGGCCAUUACAGUGCCUGCUCCACAGCUUGGGCACCACCGGCACCCUCGUGUGGGAGAGGGGAGUUCUUCAGAUGAGGAGUCUGGAGGCACACUGCCCCCUCCAGACUUUCCACCUCCACCACUGCCGGACUCAGCCAUCUUCCUGCCCCCCAGCCUGGAUCCUUUACCAGGGCCAGUGGUCCGGGGCCGUGGUGGGGCUGAGGCCCGUGGCCCACCACCUCCCAAGGCCCAUCCAAGGCCUCCACUGCCCCCAGGCCCCUCACCAGCCAGCACUUUCCUGGGGGAAGUGGCCAGUGGGGAUGACCGGUCCUGCUCGGUGCUGCAGAUGGCCAAGACGCUGAGCGAGGUGGACUAUGCCCCUGCUGGGCCUGCACGCUCAGCGCUCCUCCCAGGCCCCCUGGAGCUGCAGCCCCCCCGGGGACUGCCCUCGGACUAUGGCCGGCCCCUCAGCUUCCCUCCACCCCGCAUCCGGGAGAGCAUCCAGGAAGACCUGGCAGAGGAGGCUCCGUGCCUGCAGGGCGGGCGGGCCAGCGGGCUGGGCGAGGCAGGCAUGAGUGCCUGGCUGCGGGCCAUCGGCUUGGAGCGCUAUGAGGAGGGCCUGGUGCAUAAUGGCUGGGACGACCUGGAGUUUCUCAGUGACAUCACCGAGGAGGACUUGGAGGAGGCUGGGGUGCAGGACCCGGCUCACAAGCGCCUCCUUCUGGACACCCUGCAGCUCAGCAAGUGAUAGCGGAGGCACCACGAAGCUGUGAACUCAGAGCCCCUCCCUGCUACCAAGGCCCAGCUAUGGCCCCAGGGUUGAAAAGUUAUGAGGGUCAGGGCAGUAUCUCUCUGCCUAUUUAUUGGGGUGCCUAUUUAUUGGGGAUCUGCAUUCCCCGCUGCCCAAUCAUUUGCAAUGCCCUAAUUAGGGCAUCCUGCCCCUCGCCUUUUAGGCUCAGGACGGAAGGUCAGUUGCCAUGGUUACCGAGGACCCUGGUUACUCUGGUGCUGUCCUGUUUUACUGGACCCCGCCUCCCAGCCCCAGGGGUGCCUGUGGGGGUCCAUUUGGGUACGUCUGGGCCCCCACUUUCACCAGUUUCUGCGGCCUUCCACCGGGCCUGAACCACAGCGGAGGAGCUCCGCUAAGACCUCCCCACCCCCGCUGGGGGUGGGGGCGGGUGUCCGUCCGGAAAUGAAGGAAUAGCCCGAGGACCGGGCUGGGGUUUAUUUAAACUGUUCUGUGUGGGUCUGGGGAGGGAGAGCACCUUAAUAUUAUUGGGGUUGGUUGGGGUGGGGCAGGAUCUCAGCCAUAAAGUGCCAGUUUGCUUAGUUCUCACUGUCUCCUGGUCUGUGCUGCCCUGCUCUGGGGAUGCACGGCGGCAGGGUGGGGGAGGGAGGUUCCUCGCAGGUCUCAGCCCGGGACAGGGUCUUGCAAGCAGCCUCCUGGGCAGUCGUAAGGGUUGCGGCGUGAUGUCUUCAAUAAAUUAAGUUUUAUUUGGAUUGAGUAAAACUUCAAUAAAUUACAAGUUUUUCAAAGAAAAA